CGUUUCCGGUUGGCUCCGGUUGCAGAGUUGAGUGUCCUGAGAGGUCAGAUUGCUGUCAGGUGCUUGUUCCCGCUUCUGCCACACGCAAAAUUGUCUUUGUUUGCCUUUGGAUCGCAAAGGCAGAAGAACAGCAUCACUAAAAGUAAUAACAGUUCAUUUGUUUUUUAUGUUCUAAUAUUCAUAUAAUCACAGUUUUUAAUACGAGGAAGUUAAGAUAUAUACUUGAUAGUCUUCGGUAAACUAAAAUUGCAUGUAGUGGAAGUAGCAUUAUCUUCUUAUUUCUUUCUUAGGGAAAGGAUACCAGCACAUUUUCUUAGAGCCAGCUUCCUUUAGUGGAGGUUGAUCUUCAUGAGACUUUUAGAUUCACUUCAGACAUAGAUAGCUUUUAAAAUUUUUGGUUGCAUGUUUUUUCUUUAUUUAACUAAUUUCCUUACUGUUAUUAUUUGAGCUGCUCUGAAACGGAAAUAACCACCAUUUUUCAGUCCUCAGCACAAUUUAAGUCAAUUUUUCUAUUUUUAUUUUUUAUUGUCAAGUAUAUAUACAGAAGGGUGUAUAAAACAUACAUUUUAAAAAAUUAUAACUAACAGAAGCAGACACUCCUGUAUCCACCUCUUAGAUUAGAAAAUAAAGCAUUGCCAAUAACUUAGAACAUGCAGUCUUAACAGGGGUGAUUUUACAUUUCAAGGGGUUGAAAAUUGGUGGGGCCGGGGUCGGAAUCUUAGUUACUACAAUGAUUUGUGUCCCUCCAAAGGGCCACAGUAUAUAAACAGUUAUACAGUAUAUAUGUAGUGUUAAAUUUUCAUGGCGGGGGGUGUGAUUAGGAAUAAAAUGUCUAGAAAGGUUCCUUACAGGGACAAUAGUUAAAAAUUGGUUGAAAAACACUGCCUUAGAAUCUCCCAGUAUGUUUCUGUGAUUCCAUCUCCUCCACCAAGAGACAUGGCCCAUGAACAUGGACAUGAGCAUGGACAUCAUAAAAUGGAACUUCCAGAUUAUAGACAAUGGAAGAUAGAAGGGACACCAUUAGAAACUAUCCAGAAGAAGCUGGCUGCAAAAGGGCUAAGGGAUCCAUGGGGCCGCAAUGAAGCUUGGAGAUACAUGGGUGGCUUUGCAAAGAGUGUUUCCUUUUCUGAUGUAUUCUUUAAAGGAUUCAAAUGGGGAUUUGCUGCAUUUGUGGUAGCUGUAGGAGCUGAAUAUUACCUGGAGUCCCUGAAUAAAGAUAAGAAGCAUCACUGAAGAUAAUACCUGGAAGCAUCAUAGUGGUUUCUUAACUCUCCAAAAUAAGAUUUCUUCUCUGUAGCCUACUUGUCUGGUUUAUCCCUUACAGAAUAUUAGUAAGAUUUAAUCAAUUAAAAUAUAUAUAUAUGCCAA